GCUUCGCUCUCCCCGGCCAACCGCCCGGACCUCGGCGCUUUCUUCUAGGAUCCGCAUGAAUCGCUUUGGGCUAUCGGAAGAGCUAUCCCCAGUUCUCGGGAGAAAGAGUCCGCGACCAGCGUCUGACCUCUCACUCAGAGUCCCCAGUCCUGCCUUAGUUUCCCCAGCGACCCUGAAUUUGGAGUUGCUGUCUCUAAGUGAAAGCUGAACCUGCAACCCCUUGAGGGUUUCAGCCGCAGAGGGGCGGGAGAAAGGGCCUGGUUGGUAGGCGGGCUCAGCGGUUCGCGCCCAGUUAGCCCCGAGCUUCGGAGACCCGAGAGACCAGAGGAUGGCUGACACGAAGGGGCACCCGAGACAGCGCCUGGGCUUUUUCCCGCCCGCGGUUCCACCGCUCUGAAACCGAUUUCUAACAGAGAGAGACAUAGUCUUGCUCUGUUACCCAUGCUGGAGUACGGUGGCGAGAUCACGACUCACUACAACUUUGAAUUCCUGGAUUCAAGCAAUCCUCCCAUCUCAGCCUCCUGAGUAGCUAAGGACUACAGGGCGACUUUGUCAGUACCCCAAACUGUCCCCGCAUGAGGUCACUCUGCACGGUCACGUGCUCGAGCCCGCGGGAGCGCCACAUCGCCAGCCGCACCCCUCCACCCCCAACCUGCCCACGUGACCCGGCCUAGUUUCUCCAGGCCCGUCCCUACGUCUCACUCGGGAAGCCCCGCCCCACGCUGAGCGCUCCGCCUGCGACCCUCCGCCACUUACCCACCCCGGCUCAAGCACGACCCGUGGAUCCACGUGCUUUUUCUUGUCCAAUGGGAGCCGGCUCCCGGGCGCGAAGGGGCGGGGAGGAAAGGAACGACUGUGCUACGUUGCCAGAAGGGGCGGGACCUGCAACGUCCGACAGAACGAGGGGACGUAACGGAGGCAGGUUGGAGCCGCUGCCGUCGCCAUGACCCGCGGUAACCAGCGUGAGCUCGCCCGCCAGAAGAAUAUGAAAAAGCAGAGCGACUCGGUUAAGGGAAAGCGCCGAGAUGACGGGCUUUCUGCUGCCGCCCGCAAGCAGAGGGACUCGGAGAUCAUGCAGCAGAAGCAGAAAAAGGCAAACGAGAAGAAGGAGGAACCCAAGUAGCUUUGUGGCUUCGUGUCCAACCCUCUUGCCCUUCGCCUGUGUGCCUGGAGCCAGUCCCACCACGCUCGCGUUUCCUCCUGUAGUGCUCACAGGUCCCAGCACCGAUGGCAUUCCCUUUGCCCUGAGUCUGCAGCGGGUCCCUUUUGUGCUUCCUUCCCCUCAGGUAGCCUCUCUCCCCCUGGGCCACUCCCGGGGGUGAGGGGGUUACCCCUUCCCAGUGUUUUUUAUUCCUGUGGGGCUCACCCCAAAGUAUUAAAAGUAGCUUUGUAAUUCCUUGAGCGCCUGGUUUGACUGGGGACUUGGGGGGAUGGGGUUGGAAGAAUGACUGCCCUUUCCCACCAAAAAAGGGAGAACUCUUUAGAUUCAGAUUGUGGGUAUGUAGACUUAAUAAGUGAAACAUCACAGAAGAAGCCUUUAUUAUACAAUGACAACCAAACAAGUACUCCGGAUAUGCAGUAGAGGAAUCCUCUAAGAACCAUAGAGACUUCUUUUCUGUGAUUUUUGUUCCCCACCCUUGAACACCAUCUCUAGGAUGGAGUUGGCCUAAGAGUGAAUGCUGCAAGAUCUGUGUUUAUGCCUCUUUUCCUCAUUCUUCCUCAGUUUGUUCGUCUGCUUGAAAGUUGGCCAAAAAAUCCUGCUGCUCACCGACUUCCCGUGGUCAGCUGCUGUCAAGCGUUCACUUUCUCUUCUGUCAUUCCUCAUGGAAUGAGGGUGGUUUUGUCUUCCCGCUUCCCUUGACCUCAAAAUCAGGAUUAAAACCUGGGGUAGCCUCUGUGCUCCUUUCUUCUAUGCCCUGGUUUGUUCUGUGGUUCUGGGCUUCUUAUAUCCGUGUGCCCAGGGCUGAACUCCUUAUUUUCCUUUCUCCAAGGGCAGAGCCGAGUCUUCAGUCCCUGUUGGUCUUUCCCCACCCCCACUUCCAGCCCAAGAGCCAGGAAAGGGCUGGUGCCACACUGUCUGCUGGGAUCAGCGGUGGUUCUUUGAGCUGCUGAUUUGGGUGUUAGGCUCUUGAGCUGGGAUGCAGAUGUAACAGUAGCUCCAGUGAGUCAGACACUCUGCCCAGCACAUUAGACUGUGUUUGACCACUUCUUCCAGUUCAUAGUAUUGACUUCAGCCCAAACGGAGAUAACUCCCUGUGUGUCCUUGAGGUAUUGAGCUGGGCUGGACAGCUCCCCUUGAGCCAACUCUAGGAGUACAAUGUCAGGGGAACCCCAGUUUGUGAAAAGGACUUAGACUGGAGGAUAUUUGUUAUCUGGGGAUAUGAUGCGGUGGCGGCGGCGCCUCAAGAUAAGGGGCUGGGGUUUCUGGGUGGGGGGCCAACAGAGUGGUGCCAGUAACAGCCCCAGAUAGAGGAGUACGCAGGCCCAGCAUGAGGCAACCUUGACCCAGAAGGUGGCCCAGCUACCCUUGAUGAAGGUCUUUUCCAGUUCUGCUCCCUCAUAGCUGUGUAACCAAAGGCUCUGGUUAGAGAAUAUGAAGGGCCUUAGCUUUUAGACCUGUUCUACCUCCUCACCAAAUAUAAUGGCAGACCCAUGUGUGUCUGGAAUGGCCUUGAAUUGCUCUUUCCUUAAAAUAGCUAGCUCUUCAGGAGAGUAUCUAAGGCCCACUCCAUCUUACCUGAACCAGUUGGUAAGGGUAACCAUGACAUAGAGUGAGGCAAGGAAGAAGACGAAGUGGAAGGCAGAAUAGUUGUAGGAAAGAUGCUGGACUUGGACUGGAGGAGCUGGAGGGGUUUCUUGGUCAGCUGGCCUCGCAGCCCCACCCCUUUGCCCUGGAGAGAGGAAAUGGCUGCUGGGAGCAGAGCUGCUGAAACACCUCUUCCCCUCUCCCCCAACUACCUUUGUUAAGGCUCUUGAGGGUUCUUAUGGCACUCCACAGAGAUCUACCACUUCUUAUGGUUCCUCACUUGGCACUCACCUUUGUCUGCCUCCACUGUUUCAGGGCAGCAGAAACACAGUGAGGGCUUCUGCAAAACAGAACGCAGGUUUUGGAAUGGUCUUAAAAGAUGUGAGGGUGUUAAUCUAGGAAACUUCCCCCGUGAAAAGAUUGGUCUAGUAUUAAAAAGUGGAGGCACACCUGGGUUCAAAUUCUAGCUCCAGCAUAUAAGUGGCUGUGCAGACUUUGGUAAGAUGUUUAAUCUUUUGUGCCUCGAUUUCUCCAUUUGUAAAAUGGAGCAAAUACCUACCUCACAGGGUUGUUGUGAGGGUUAAAUUAAAUGAGAUUAUGUAAAAGUAUCUAGCACAGUUGCCUAGCACAUUGUGGGUACUCAAUAAAAGGUAACAGCAGCUAUAAUCUGAGCAUUCUGGGUA